UCUUUCCCCUACUCAGAUCUUCCUGUCCUUGUUUCUUCUGUCUUUGUCUUAUUUUAGAUGGGCAGGUUUUCUGGAUGACUGAUUACUCAAAUAUUUUAGGUGUUUCCCACACUCAGAUUAUAAGACAGAAAGCAAAAUUUGUUUUAAGGGUGUAUGUCUGUUAACAACCAACCGCUGCUCUAAUGCCAGAGCUUCCAGUUACUAAUUAACUUUAUCCAGCAGGUAGCCCAGCAGAGCUGGAAGUCCAGUUCCCAGGAGACCUCAGAAGUCCCGAGUUGUGGCUCUGCCGUUGGUGGCCAUGGGGACUUCGGCAAGAGAGUUGACUGAGUUCAGUGGUUGUCUGCUAUGACUCGAUGCUUUAGAAACUGAAGCUGUAUCUAGGACUGAGGAGGCCUAAGCUCAAAUCCAGAUUGACUUAGAGUUCCAGGGUUUUAGACCUGCAAGAGACCUGGGAGGUCUCACCAGCCCAACCUCUGUAUUUUAGAGGUGAAGAAACUGUGACUCAGAGAUUGAGCAAAUGACUAUGUGUUUGCCUAAGAUCACAUAGUUAGUUAAUGGUAGAGUGAAGACAGGAACCCAGUUCCAACCUCCAGCUCCAUAUGCUGUCACUGAGAUAAAAACCUUAGAAUUCCUGGCAGCCUUGAAGAUGUAUACGUGUGUAUGCAUCUGUAUGUAUUUAGAAUUGUGUGUUUAUAUGUUAAGCACGCAACAUUUAUAUUGUGUAUUUUAUAAAGUAAAUAUUUAUAGAACACUUAUAUGUUCUAUAAUAUGGAUCUAUGAAUUUAGGCUUAUGGAUUCCAUUAGGUAAAGUUGUACAUAUUUUUAGUAUAGUAACUGGUGUUAGCUAAGUUGCCAACUACAAUACCGACGAGUUCUCAGGCUGGGCUGUGGAAUGGUCGCUUAGCAGGAAUUCGGCAGAAUGCAGAUGGUGGAAGGGCUGAUUUCUCAUCACGUCUUCCAACUGUGUCCUUGAGCAAGCUCCUUAUCUCCCUGAGUACCGGGCUCUGCUUCUGUAAAACACUGAUGAGAGCUACUGCUUGUUGAACACUUUCUUUUUGCAGCACUGCUGAGCUCAUUACAUAUGGUGUGACAUCUACUCCUCCUGUAGUGCACACCAGGGUAUGCCCAUUUCACAGAUGAGGAGACUGAGCCUCACACAGGCCACGUGCUGCUGGGUCUCAGUCCUCCACUUCCCGUGUCCUCUGGAAGUUGUCAGGAGCAAUGUUGCGCUUGUACGUGUUGGUAAUGGGAGUUUCUGCCUUCACCCUUCAGCCUGCGGCACACACAGGACGGUCCCAGGAGAAGAAGAGACACGGAUGUGGGCCCAGGACGGUGCUCUGUGGCUUCUGCCAGCCUUGCAGGAGGACUCUGGCACCUACGUCUGCACUACUAGAAAUGCUUCUUACUGUGACAAAAUGUCCAUUGAGCUCAGAGUUUUUGAGAAUACAGAUGCUUUCCUGCCGUUCAUCUCAUACCCGCAAAUUUUAACCUUGUCAACCUCUGGGGUAUUAGUAUGCCCUGACCUGAGUGAAUUCACCCGUGACAAAACUGACGUGAAGAUUCAAUGGUACAAGGAUUCUCUUCUUUUGGAUAAAGACAAUGAGAAAUUUCUAAGUGUGAGGGGGACCACUCACUUACUCGUACACGAUGUGGCCCUGGAAGAUGCUGGCUAUUACCGCUGUGUCCUGACAUUUGCCCAUGAAGGCCAGCAAUACAACAUCACUAGGAGUAUUGAGCUACGCAUCAAGAAAAAAAAAGAAGAGACCAUUCCUGUGAUCAUUUCCCCCCUCAAGACCAUAUCAGCUUCUCUGGGGUCAAGACUGACAAUCCCGUGUAAGGUGUUUCUGGGAACCGGCACACCCUUAACCACCAUGCUGUGGUGGACGGCCAAUGACACCCACAUAGAGAGCGCCUACCCGGGAGGCCGCGUGACCGAGGGGCCACGCCAGGAAUAUUCAGAAAAUAAUGAGAACUACAUUGAAGUGCCAUUGAUUUUUGAUCCUGUCACAAGAGAGGAUUUGCACAUGGAUUUUAAAUGUGUUGUCCAUAAUACCCUGAGUUUUCAGACACUACGCACCACAGUCAAGGAAGCCUCCUCCACGUUCUCCUGGGGCAUUGUGCUGGCCCCACUUUCACUGGCCUUCUUGGUUUUGGGGGGAAUAUGGAUGCACAGACGGUGCAAACACAGAACUGGAAAAGCAGAUGGUCUGACUGUGCUAUGGCCUCAUCAUCAAGACUUUCAAUCCUAUCCCAAGUGAAAUAAAUGGAAUGAAAUAAUUCAAACACAAACUCCGUACGUCUUCUCUUAUGGAAGUGGCUGUGUCUUUUUGAGGGACUCUGUUCUUUGCCUCAGUUGUCUACCAAAGGUGCCACAUUUAUAGUGGCUUUGUAGUAAAGGACUAAAGUCUUA